AUGGAAGUGGCACCGACGGGGAGAGCUCAGGACGCCGUGGAUAUCAUGGAAAUGGCACCGACGGGGAGAGCUCAGGACGCCGUGGAUAUCAUGGAAAUGGCACCGACGGGGAGAGCUCAGGACGCCGUGGAUAUCAUGGAAAUGGCACCGACGGGGAGAGCUCAGGACGCCGUGGAUAUCAUGGAAAUGGCACCGACGGGGAGAGCUCAGGACGCCCUGGAUAUCAUGGAAAUGGCACCGACGGGGAGAGCUCAGGACGCCGUGGAUAUCAUGGAAAUGGCACCGACGGGGAGAGCUCAGGACGCCGUGGAUAUCAUGGAAAUGGCACCGACGGGGAGAGCUCAGGACGCCGUGGAUAUCAUGGAAAUGGCACCGACGGGGAGAGCUCAGGACGCCGCGGAUAUCAUGGAAAUGGCACCGACGGGGAGAGCUCAGGACGCCGUGGAUAUCAUGGAAAUGGCACCGACGGGGAGAGCUCAGGACGCCGCGGAUAUCAUGGAAAUGAGCUUAGAACACCGUGGAUAUCAUGGAAGUGGCACCGACGGGGAGAGCUUAGAAUGCCGUGGAUAUCAUGGAAAUGGCACUGACAGGGAGAGCUUAGAACGCCGUGCAUAUCAUGGAAAUGGCACCGAUGGGGAGAGUUUAGAACACCAUGGAUAUCAUGGAAAUGGUACCGAUGGGGAGAGUUUAGAACGCCAUGGAUAUCAUGGAAAUGGCACCGACGGGGAGAGCUUAGGACACUGUGGAUAUCAUGGAAAUGGCACCGACAGCGAGAGUUUAGAAUGCUGUGGAUAUCAUGGAAAUGGCACCGAUGGGGAGAGCUUAGGACGCCGUGGAUAUCAUGGAAAUGGCACCGACGGGGAGAGCUUAGAAUGCCAUGGAUAUCAUGGAAAUGGCACCGAUGGGGAGAGUUUAGAACGCCGUGGAUAUUAUGGAAAUGGCACCGAUGGGGAGAGUUUAGAACGCCGUGGAUAUCAUGGAAAUGUCACCGACGGGGAGAGCUUAGAACGCCAUGGAUAUCAUGGAAAUGGCACCGACGGGGAGAGUUUAGAACGCCGUGGAUAUCAUGGAAAUGGCACCGACAGGGAGAGUUUAGAACGCCGUGGAUAUCAUGGAAAUGGCACCCACAGCGAGAGUUUAGAACACCAUGGAUAUCAUGGAAAUGGCACUGACAGGGAGAGUUUAGAACGCCAUGGAUAUCAUGGAAAUGGCACCGACAGGGAGAGCUUAGAACGUCGUGGAUAUCAUGGAAAUGGCACCAACAGGGAGAGUUUAGAACACCGUGGAUAUCAUGGAAAUGGCACCCACAGCGAGAGUUUAGAACACCGUGGAUAUCAUGGAAAUGGCACCCACAGCGAGAGUUUAGAACACCAUGGAUAUCAUGGAAAUGGCACCGACAGGGAGAGCUUAGAACGUCGUGGAUAUCAUGGAAAUGGCACCAACAGGGAGAGUUUAGAACACCGUGGAUAUCAUGGAAAUGGCACCCACAGCGAGAGUUUAGAACACCGUGGAUAUCAUGGAAAUGGCACUGACAGCGAGAGUUUAGAACACCGUGGAUAUCAUGGAAAUGGCACUGACAGCGAGAGUUUAGAACACCGUGGAUAUCAUGGAAAUGGCACCAACAGGGAGAGUUUAGAACACUGUGGAUAUCAUGGAAAUGGCACCCACAGCGAGAGUUUAGAACACCGUGGAUAUCAUGGAAAUGGCACUGACAGCGAGAGUUUAGAACACCGUGGAUAUCAUGGAAAUGGCACUGACAGCGAGAGUUUAGAACGCUGUGGAUAUCAUGGAAAUGGCACCCACAGCGAGAGUUUAGAACACCGUGGAUAUCAUGGAAAUGGCACCGACGGGGAGAGUUUAGAACGCCGUGGAUAUCAUGGAAAUGGCACCAAUGGGGAGAGUUUAGAACACCAUGGAUAUCGUGGAAAUGGCACUGAUGGGGAGAGUUUAGAACACCGUGGAUAUCAUGGAAAUGGCACCCACAGCGAGAGUUUAGAACACCAUGGAUAUCAUGGAAAUGGCACUGACAGGGAGAGUUUAGAACACCGUGGAUAUCAUGGAAAUGGAUUUCAGAAAGGCUUUUGUAUGUUAGUUUUCAGCCAAGUCAAGAAGUGAGAUGCAUCCACAUCUGGCUGCAUGCUUGUAAUUAGAAUCUGACUUUCAAAUUCGUCUCAAUGUGUGUGGAAGUCUUAGAACCACAGUUCAUCCUGCAGUUUGUUCAGUUCUGAUUAAAAGCACUCACUCCACAUGUGCCAGGCACUGCAAUAGGCUUUGGGGAUACAAAGGUUAAUAGAAGAGUUCAUGCCCUCAAAGAGCUCAUUCAGUCCUAAUACACCUUCAAACCGGAAGUGUCCCUGCUGACACAGAGCAAAAUGACCACUUUUAUGAGCGACAUGAAACUGGGAAGGGGACCCAGAUAUCCUCCUGUCCCCAUCCCCGUCCCCCAGCACAGGGCCUGUGUCCCAGCAGCCUGCUGGUAGACCAAAGCAGCCAAGGUAAAAGGCCAAUCCCGGCUCUCCCCCCAGCCAGCUUCGCACCACUCAAUCUGUGGGAAAUUGAGGGCAUCAUAUUUGGACCAUGACUUACUUGUGGUUGUUUGUUUAAUUGGUUUUGAUGAGUUUGGUUUGCUUUUCUCUCCUUGUACGAUUUGCCCAUUUUCUGUCCUCGGUUUUUCCAUGUCUGAGUAAUAGUCUUCUUUUGUCUUAUGCCCAUCCCCCGUUUUUGCCAGAGCCUUCCACCCUCCUGCCUCAGUCUCCACAGCCUGCUCCCUCGGCCUCCUCUGGGCUGGCUGUCCUGGGUCAGCGGUGAGUUCUUCUUUCUUGGGUUACAUGCUUUGCGGCUUCUUUGCUGAAUGCAGUCAGGGGCAGGGGCAGGGGCAGGCCCAGGGAGCUCGCCUGUCUUGCCCUACAGAGUCUUCAGCUCCCAGCUCUUAGCUUGACCCAAACGAGAUACUUUCACGCAUGUGUGUUACAAACUGGAGCAAAACCGCGCACUUGGCAACUAAGGAGAGUUAGCCUGCAAAGAGAAAUCUGGGAUGGGUGGAAUCUGUGACUUCAGUUAUGACGGACUUUCAGGUGAAAAAAUGUGUAUUUAUUUUGAGUGGACCCAGAUGGCAGAACAAGGAUGAUUGGAUACAGUUGUGGAGAUGUAGUUCCUGCACUAUGGACAGCUGUGGGCUGUGCUCCCCGGCAAGGAAAAGGCGAGCAGCCACCCCAGAGCGCCAGUGCAGAGGCUCCCUUGGCACUAGGGUGUGGGGCAGGUGUGGGCUCCUCCACCACAGGGCAGUGGGUGAGGAGCACCAGACCCACAGGAUGGCUUCCAGGACCAGUCUGUAGCUCUUGGACUUUAAGGGCAUACUGUUCUCUUUUAAAGAAAAGUUAAAACUGUGGCCUGAUGCGCCUUUUUUUUUUUUUUUUUUUUUUGAGAUGGAGUCUCAUUCUGUCACCCAGGCUGGAGUGCAGUGACGCGAUCUCGGCUCACUACAACCUCUGCCUCCUGGGUUCAAGUGAUUCUUCUGCUUCAGCCUCCCAAGUAGCCAGGACUGCAGGUGUCCACCACUACUCCUGGCUAAUUUUUUUUCUUCUUUGUAUUUUUAGUAGAGACGGGGUUUUACCAUGUUGGCCAGGCUGGUCUUGAACCCCUGACCUCAAGUGAUCACAUGCCUCGGCCUCCCAAAGUGCUGGGAUUACAGGUGUGAACCACCAUGCCUGGCCCUGAUGCACUUUCAAAGUUUUCCAUAACAGUGAGUUUUAAGUAGCCAAGCUCUAAAUCUAAAUAAUUGCCCAAGGGUGAUGGUUAAGGAGACUGCUGAGUGGGAAGAACAGAGAGUAGGGAGGCUUGGGAAGACCAGGUGAGGAGGAGCAGUCAGUCAGAGAAGAGCCUUGGCAGGAACUGAGGAGGGAGGCGUGGACAGCAGCAUCCGUGGGAAGGAGGACUCCAGAGGCUCCUGACUUGGGUGAGGGAGCCAGCCACAGUGGGCCCUGGUCUUCCAGCCAGAUGGGACCGCUUGCCAGAGGAUCCUUGGGGUGUCACAUUUCUAGCUGGAAACUUCUGUGGCUGGUGGCACCCUUGCCCGAGUUUUGCUUGGGCCCACUGGGCUUGUUCUGCCCACUCAGCCUGGCAUGCUGCACUCAACUCACGCUACUGGCCUGGAUCCCACACCUGCCAAGAGCGAGUCAGGCACAGAGCAGUGAGGGGUGUGUGAGUGAGCAUGGGGUCCAGCCACUGUGCAGUCAGGCACACCCGCAGCUGCUGCAAGGUGGGCAGCUCCAGUGCUGGCAUGGGCGCCCACUCUCUGCAAGGCUGCAGCUGGACCAGGUGCACUGCAAGCAGCUUCCACAGCUGGCACUGGGGAAUGCAGUAUGCCAGGAACCACAGGGCCCCAAAGAGGGAGUCCAACUCAGAAGGGGCAGGGCUCCUGCUUGUUCCUGGCCUGGGGGGCUCCCAAGUCUAGGCUCCCUGAAGGGCUGCAGCUCUUCUCUCCUUCUCUUCCCCCAUAGCAUGGCAAGCAAGGGGCAUGUCUCAGCCCUGUUUGUGUUAUACCAGCUCUUUUAGCCUUGCCAUUUGACGGGUCCCAAGUUCUUGUCCUGUGACCAGGAAGAAUGAGGUCUGCAGACAAGUGGAGGGUGAGCAAGAGGAAGACGAGCUUUAUUGAGCGAUACAACGGCUCAGAGGAGACCCGCAGGGGCAGCUCCUUUCCACAGCCAGGGUGUCACAACGCGUGUUCAGCUCCUAGCACAGAGGAGACCGUAGAGUGGGAAGCUCCUCUUGGCAGGCAGGCCAUCCUGUCAUCUCUGAGGCUCUCAGCAGAGAGGAGGCCCUGGAGUGGGUUGCUCCUGUCUGCAGACGGGCCAUCCCUUUGUGCCUGCGGCUCUCAGCAGAGAGGAGGCCCUGGAGUGGGCUGUUGCUCUCUGCAGGCAGGUCCUCUUGUUGUCUCCCCAGCUCUCAGCAGAGAGGAGGCCAUGGAAUGGGUAGCUCCUCUCUGCAUCUGGUUGCCCUGAUGUCUGCUCAGCUCUGGUUGAGCCUAGGGCUUUUAUGGGCCUUAGAGGGGAGGAAGUGCACUGUGAUUGGUACAUUGGCAGUCAUGGGUAAAGGCACCAGAAGUUCCCACUCUGGUCUGCAGGACUGGCAGCCCAGUCCCCAGCCUUCAGGACCUCCCUGGCCUGAAGGUGGGGGCCUCACCAGGGACCUGCCCUCUUCCACCCAGGAACUUGUCUGCGUCCUGCUGCUAUUCAUGGUGUCCAGGCUAUAGGUGCCAAGGGGUGCCUGCAGGCCAGUGCCAAGCUACCCUCAGCCCACCCUUGGCUUCCCUCCUAUUCUCGGUGCUUAAAGUCUGGAGGGUGCUGAGGCAGCAGGGGGCUGGUGUAUUAGCACUGCCCUGAGCGUGUGCACACCUGGCCAGGCUGCAACAGUGCCCAGGCUCGCCCUGACUUUACUCUGAGAUCAAAGUGGACACUGACAGCAGGGAGAAGCCAGGCAGCAGAAGCAGGCACUUCCAAACCUGCGAAGGCCGGGGAUGGGGCUUCCUGGGCCCCCUAGAGUGCAGAGAUGCCUGGGUCUGCAGCCAUGGUUUGGGUGGCUGUAGCUGCGCCUAGGAGAGGGGCUUCUCUCUGCUCCCGGCUUCCAGGAGCACAGGGAUGCCUGGGUCUGCAGCCAUGACUUGGGCAGCUGCAUCUGUGCCCAGAGGGGUGGGGCUCCUGCCUGCUCCAUGGAGCAGAAGGCCUGGAUCUGCAGCUGGGACUUGGGUGGGGCUUCUGCCUGCUCUGUGGAGCAGGAGGUCUGGGUCUACAGCUGUGACUUCAGUGGCUGCAGCUGUGCCCAGGAGAGUGGGGCACCCAUCUGCUCCCGGCCCGAGAGCACAGGGAUGCCUAAGUCUGCAGAGAGCUACCACCCAACUCGGAAGGGGCAGGGCUCCUGCUUGUCCGCAGCUCCUGCCAGUUCCAUGGAGCAUGCAGCCCUGGCUGUGCCUCCCUGCUGCAGCUGGCAUGAUGGCACCAGCCACUUUAGAUGGACCGUGGUGUCAUCACUGAGACCCUGUCUUGACACAGCUGUCAGGACACUCUCUAGCCACACUUGCCUUCCUGCUGCCAGUGCCGCCGUGGCUCAGGUGGCUGCAGUUCCUUGAGAUGUCCCAGUGGGUCCUGGGUGAGCCCAUCCAGCUGAUGGGCCAUGAGGCAACAGGCAAGUGGACAGGCCAGCACUGUCCCCCUUCCUCUUCUUCUGCCCCUUCAACUGCAGGCUGGAAAAUUCAUAUGUUACCAGGAAAACAGCCGGCUACCCAGGGCUAUUUACCUCAGGGGCCAAGCUUCCCGUGGGAUGAGAUCGUUGGGCUCAGAGAACGUGUUGAGCAAACACAGUACUUUCUGUGAGCUGGGUUAGGUUGUAAAAGCCUUACAAAGAGUAACCUAAUCAUCAGCACAACCAACAGAAAUAGAUGUUUGUUUUUUUAAUCAUCAUUGCAUUUCACAAAUUAAACAGAGGGUAAGUCACUUGCCCAGUGGCACACAGCUCUCAGGUGACAGACUGGGAUUUGGAUCCAGGCAGGCUUGUACAGACUCCAGAGUCCCAAAUAUGGCUUCAUCCACAGUGUCGGAGCAGCAGCGAGGGCUCUAAGACCACCCAGCUCUCUUCCUGGCUAUUUUUUCCAUGCUACUCAUCCCAAAACUUGAUCUCACAUUGCUCUGUUUCUUUCUCUGCCUCCAUGCUUGAUGCAUUUACUUAAUCUUUCGCAGGAUGGGUCAUUACUUUUUGCAAUAGCACACUCAAAGGUAAUGACCAAGAUAAAUUGAAAAGAGGAUUCAACAGUAUUCAUUGUAAGAUUGAAUGGGAUAUAAAAUACGUAAUCAGCACUUGUGAGGAAUAUCACUAGAUUCUCUUCUUCCUACUCCCCCUCCUUUUUUUUUUUUUUUUUUUUUUGCAUUAAAACCCGGGAAUUUGAUGUUGAUUGUGGCCUAAAUGUUAAGCAUAUUCUGGAUUUUCUACACCGUUCUGACACCACAGGUACUUGUUUCUUUCUCAGAAGGCAGGUGAAGCUCAGCUGUGUGGGGCUGUGCUUGGUGGCAGUGUGGGAAACGUGUGGAACUCACCAUGGUGUUAGCAGCUUUUACUAGCCGUUUGCUUGGAAAACAGUCUCCGAUCUGCACUUGCACACCCACCACGAUGCCUUCUCCCCAUGGCUCUGUGGACACCAGGAGGUCAGGGCACAGAGGACGUGCGACUUGUGCUCCUGUCUUGCUGCACAGUCUAAAGACCUCACGUACGUUUUGAAUGUUCAACCACUAUUAGAGUGAGAAAUGGCAUCCAAGAUGCUUUUACUGAGGAACAUUGACAACUGGAAAACAAAUCAAGCUUGGAUUCCAGGGAACACUGUCCAGAUUUCCUGUUUUAUGAAUUUUACCAUUCACUCUUAAGGCUGUUAGGUUUGAAUAACUUGAUAAAUGAUCAAGAGAAAACCAUGCAGCAUUAUGUUCACUGCCAAGUAAUAUGGACGUAGAGGAUGGCAGAAUUCUGUAAAACCACUUCUGGAGUUCAACAUUUAACCGAGCACAUUUUACUUACCUGUUACCAGUGUGUCGCUUGGAAUGUCUUCUAUUAGGCAUUUCUCCUCACGUUCCCCUGCGUGGAAAUAAAAGGCAGUUGAAAAUGGAAAACCAAAA